GAGGGCUGUGCGCGGUGGCGCGGGGGCGGAAAGCCGCAGGUCGGGCUCUCACCUGACCGUGGCUCGUUCCUAGAAGCGCAGUUUCCUAGUCGCUGCCUGUAGGGUCCACACUCGGACAGUAAAUUUGUGUUCAUCGCCGGGCGUGGUGGGGCCUGUGGUCCCAUCUACUCCGUAGGCUGAGGUGGAAGGAUCGCUUUAGCCCAGGAGGUGGAGGCUGCAGUGAGCCGAGAUCGCGCCACUGCACCCCUGUCUGGGCGACGGCGAGACCCCGUCUCCAAAAUGAUGAUAACGAUAACUACCAUUUUUGAGUACUAUGUGCUAGAUGCUUUUCAUGUGUUAUCUGAUUACUGUAGCCCUACCAGGUGCAGCCUGGCACCGUUUUAUUUCACUUAGAACUGAGAUUCCGAUAAAGUAACUUUUCCAAGGCAAGAGGUAGUCAGAGGCUGAGGAAUGAUUCAAAUUUAAGUCCAGCUCCAAAGCACCGGCCCAGUGUAGUCUGCAGAGUUCCAGCCCCAUAGAGCCACAUGGAGGAUGCGAGUGACAAUCGCCAAUCAACAAAUAGUUGAUGUAGAUUUCUUUAGUGAUGACUUAAUUGUUAGGGCCUGCUGGGAUUGUUCGAAAACCAGGGCUGAGAGUGGAAAGUGCAACUUCUGGGUGCAGGAGGAGCAAACAGGGCAACUGAUAGCAGUUUCCACAUUAGGAAGCUGCCCAGAGCUAAUUAUGACUGUCACAACACAGCCCCCCCUUAACUCAACACACCAAAAUAAAGAGCUUCGGUUCCGCUUUAGAUCCUGAAUUUGACUUCUUUGCAGGUUUAUACGAUGGUCUUAGUGUCAUGUGGGGUAAUUGUGAGGAUUUCGAUUGUAUUUAAUUCUCCAUGGAAAACCAGUACGGUUUGCUACUUUUUACAUGGCAGGGAAGGCUAAACUUUACCUCUGCCCAUCUUAGUUCGGAGUGACCCCUUUAACAAAUGAAAGGAUAACAAGAAAAAAGUUUAUUCUUGGACAGAGUACACAUCACAAGGGAUAAACCUUAAUGAGAAGUAACUUGAAAUGGUGGCUUAGAACUACAUUUGUAUACCAUCUUCAACAAAGAACUGUAGAUUUGCAGAGAAGUGACAGGACACAGGAGAGCAGUUUUAGGCUUCAAAGGGCAGGAAAUUGGGAAGGUAGAUACAUAUUCGGAAACUAAUGGAGUAAGAAUUGUUUGCAGAUUCCCCUGGUACCUUAACUGGUCUGGUAAGUCUAAAGUUAUCCCCAGUAAAGAAUUUAUAUCCUGUCUUUGGGCGGAAGAGGGGGAGGAUAGAGAGAGCUUUUCCUUCAUUUGCUGCCUCUUGUCUUCAGCUCAAAUUUGUUGUUGUUUUUAUAUCGAAGAGGCAUGUUUUGGGAUGACAUUGUGGUUUUCUUCAACACCGUUUAGGUAGUCAGAGGUACGUGGGGUUCUUUUUCCUUCUUGUUCGUUAUACUUGGUUUCUGCUCUCCCAUUCCCCAUUUAAAAAAAUUGCUUAUUUUGAUAACUCUGGGAUAGUGAAGGAAUGCUGAGAGCAAUAAUGCUCUGGUCGUAAAACACAUUCAGCUUCCGUGAACUUGUAUUUUUUCUUUUUUUUUUUUAAGUGAAAGGCAAGUUUAUUAAGAAAGUAAAGGAAUAAACAAUGGCUACCCCAUAGACAGAGCAGUUUGCAAAUAUUAUGAUUGAUAAUUUUAGGUCUUUAAGCCUUUAUCAUAUUUGAGAACAUUUAUGUAAAUUAUCUUUAAUAUUUAAUCACUAUGUUUUAAUCAUACAGCUCUCACGAUAUCCAGAAAGCAUGUUAACAGCAACUAUACCUGAGUGCAUUCAGUUCUUAAGAGAUGUGUCUGAAAUAUAUAAUACUCUAUUUUUCUUUCUGUUAAGCAGUGCCUUUUAUUUUAUUUUAUUUUUUAGGUAUUAAUAGGGGACCCUAUUACCACAUGUCUUUCUCCCUCAGUGUAUGAUAUAAUUUGUAAUCUUGGGUUUCAACUCAGAGAAAAUUGUGAUAUCAAUAGCAUUGUAACUCAGAAUGGUGAAGUAUGCUGGAAAACAAUCACAGACUGUGUGAGCUACACAGAGUCAGAGCAGGGUCUGGAUUACUGGGGAAGCGUGAGGCUGCUGGGCCCUGUGUGUGAGGCUGUCCAUUCACAUUUCUUAUCUCUGACCAAGGGGCAAUUUGAAAUUCGAUAUGCACCGUGGUUCCAGUGGACAAGUUUUCCAGAGUUAUUUCCUGAAAUAUUUGAUGCCUUGGAAAGUCUACAAUCUCCUGCUAUUUCUCUUAGCUUAAUGAAACUGACAUCGUGUCUAGAACGAGCCUUGGGUGAUGUAUUUUUACUGAUUGGGAAGGAAUGCCCCUUUCUUUUAAGAGAUCUGCUUUCAUCUGAGGAGCUUGCUCAAGUCUUCAGUCAGUCUGUGAUGAAUGUGCUAAAAGUCUUCGUUGGCUCUCCGUGUGGUCUCAACCUGCGUAACGUCUUAUGGCAUGGGUUUGCGUCACCUGAAGAAAUUCCUCCAAAAUACUGUUCAAUGAUGAUACUGUUGACGGCAGGAUUGGGUCAGUUACUGAAGAGUUACCUUCAAAACACUAAACUUACAUUGGCACAUCGCUCUUUCAUAUCUCUUACAAACCUCGAGGAUUUGAUUGUUUUUCCUGAUGUUACUUAUGAGGUGCUUUCAGUAUUAGAAGAAGUGAUGAUGAAAUCUGCUUUUAUAUUAAAAAUCAUGUUACCAUAUUGGGAAGUUGCACUGGUCAAGUUCAAGUCACACAGGUUUGCUGACUGCGCCAUAUUGUUGCUGACACAACUGGAGACUGGACUUAGGAAUGUUUUUGCCACACUUAACAGAUGUCCAAAAAGACUCCUGACUGCUGAGUCAACAGCUCUUUAUACCACCUUUGAUCAAAUAUUGGCAAAACACUUGAAUGAUGGUAAAAUCAAUCAGCUUCCUCUUUUCCUUGGAGAGCCUGCUAUGGAAUUUCUCUGGGAUUUCCUGAACCAUCAGGAGGGUCCCCGCAUAAGAGAUCAUUUAAGCCACGGGGAGAUCAACUUACAUGAAUUUUCAAAAGAAACAACUAAUCAGUUGCUUGCAUUUUCUCUUGUACUGCUACUCAGAUUCGUUGAUGACUGUCUGCUAUCAGUUUUUAAGGAAAAAUCAGCCGUAGAAUUGUUGAUUAGUCUUGCAGAAGGCUAUAGUUCUCGCUGUCAUCCGGUUUUUCAGCUUAAAAAACAGGUGCUGAGCUGUGAGGAGAGCAUCAGGGUUUGGGCUCUGCUGCCUUUCCCCGAAGAACUCACUCGGCAAGCCGUCAGAUUAGAAGAUAAUUCUGAAACAAAUGCCUGCCACUCUUUGAUUACAAAAAUGACGGAUGAGCUGUAUCACCAUAUGCCUGAGAAUCGUUGUGUGUUAAAGGACUUGGAUCGUCUUCCUACUGAGACGUGGCCCCAGCUUCUCCGUGAGCUCUGCAGCACACCUGUUCCCACCCUGUUCUGCCCCAGGAUUGUGCUGGAAGUGCUGGUUGUGCUCCGAAGCAUCAGCGAACAGUGCCGCCGUGUGUCCAGCCAGGUCACCGUUGCCUCAGAGCUGAGACACAGGCAGUGGGUGGAAAGGACGCUGCGGUCUCGCCAGCGGCAGAACUACCUGCGUAUGUGGAGUAGUAUCAGACUACUGUCCCCUGUGCUCAGCCUGAUACUGUUACUCAUUGCGCUGGAGUUGGUCAACAUUCAUGCUGUUUGUGGGAAGAAUGCGCAUGAGUAUCAGCAGUACCUAAAGUUUGUAAAGUCGAUCUUGCAGUACACGGAGAACCUGGUGGCUUACACCAGUUACGAAAAGAACAAGUGGAAUGAAACUAUCAAUCUUACACAUACAGCUUUGUUGAAAAUGUGGACUUUUAGUGAGAAGAAACAAAUGUUAAUACAUUUAGCCAAGAAAUCCACAAGUAAAGUACUCUUAUGAAAACUUGUAAGUCAGGAUGCUUUUAAUUUUAACAGAUUUUAACAGCGUGUAAAUUAAAAACCCAAAGACAGGGUGGAGUUGAGGGUC